AUCCUCCUGGGAAGCUUCAAUACAGCUGUGCAAGUCUGGAGUCUACAAGAGCCUACUAUAGACAUUCUACAACCAACCAGAAUCAUGGAACAGCCCACUUCAAGCAUCAAUGGGGAGAAGAGGAAGAGCCCCUGUGAAUCCAACAAUGAAAAUGAUGAGAUGCAGGAGACACCAAACAGGGACUUAGCCCCCGAACCGAGUUUGAAAAAGAUGAAAACGUCAGAAUAUUCAACAGUAUUAGCGUUUUGCUACAGGAAAGCUAAGAAAAUACAUUCAAAUCAACUGGAGAAUGACCAGUCCUGAGAGAACUCCAUCAAUCCAGUCCAAGAGGAGGAGGACGAAGGCCUAGACUCAGCUGAAGGAUCUUCAAAGCAGGAUGAAGACCUAGACUUACCUGAAGGCCUAGACUCAGCUGAAGGAUCUUCAAAGCAGGAUGAAGACCUAGACUUACCUGAAGGAUCUUCAAAGCAGAAUGAAGACCUAGGCUUACCUGAAGGAUCUUCAAAGCAGGAUGAAGACCUAGACUUACCUGAAGGAUCUUCACAGGAGGAUAAAGACGUAGAAUUACCUGAAGGAUCUUCACAGGAGGAUGAAGACCUAGAGAAAAAGCGAUCAUCUAGGUCAAGAAAUGAAAUCGAAAUUUCAGAAAUUACAGAAAUUCUCCAAGGAAGGAGCCAGAUAAAUAAAUAUUCUGAUU